ACAAACUUUCAGAGACAGCAGAGCACACAAGCUUCUAGGACAAGAGCCAGGAAGAAACCACCGGAAGGAACCAUCUCACUGUGUGUAAACAUGACUUCCAAGCUGGCCGUGGCUCUCUUGGCAGCCUUCCUGAUUUCUGCAGCUCUGUGUGAAGGUGCAGUUUUGCCAAGGAGUGCUAAAGAACUUAGAUGUCAGUGCAUAAAGACAUACUCCAAACCUUUCCACCCCAAAUUUAUCAAAGAACUGAGAGUGAUUGAGAGUGGACCACACUGCGCCAACACAGAAAUUAUUGUAAAGCUUUCUGAUGGAAGAGAGCUCUGUCUGGACCCCAAGGAAAACUGGGUGCAGAGGGUUGUGGAGAAGUUUUUGAAGAGGUAAGUUAUAUAUUUUUUAAUUUAAAUUUUUCAUUUAUCCUGAGACAUAUAAUCCAAAGUCAGCCUAUAAAUUUCUUUCUGUUGCUAAAAAUCGUCAUUAGGUAUCUGCCUUUUUGGUUAAAAAAAAAAGGAAUAGCAUCAAUAGUGAGUUUGUUGUACUCAUGACCAGAAAGACCAUACAUAGUUUGCCCAGGAAAUUCUGGGUUUAAGCUUGUGUCCUAUACUCUUAGUAAAGUUCUUUGUCACUCCCAGUAGUGUCCUAUUUUAGAUGAUAAUUUCUUUGAUCUCCCUAUUUAUAGUUGAGAAUAUAGAGCAUUUCUAACACAUGAAUGUCAAAGACUAUAUUGACUUUUCAAGAACCCUACUUUCCUUCUUAUUAAACAUAGCUCAUCUUUAUAUUUUUAAUUUUAUUUUAGGGCUGAGAAUUCAUAAAAAAAUUCAUUCUCUGUGGUAUCCAAGAAUCAGUGAAGAUGCCAGUGAAACUUCAAGCAAAUCUACUUCAACACUUCAUGUAUUGUGUGGGUCUGUUGUAGGGUUGCCAGAUGCAAUACAAGAUUCCUGGUUAAAUUUGAAUUUCAGUAAACAAUGAAUAGUUUUUCAUUGUACCAUGAAAUAUCCAGAACAUACUUAUAUGUAAAGUAUUAUUUAUUUGAAUCUACAAAAAACAACAAAUAAUUUUUAAAUAUAAGGAUUUUCCUAGAUAUUGCACGGGAGAAUAUACAAAUAGCAAAAUUGAGGCCAAGGGCCAAGAGAAUAUCCGAACUUUAAUUUCAGGAAUUGAAUGGGUUUGCUAGAAUGUGAUAUUUGAAGCAUCACAUAAAAAUGAUGGGACAAUAAAUUUUGCCAUAAAGUCAAAUUUAGCUGGAAAUCCUGGAUUUUUUUCUGUUAAAUCUGGCAACCCUAGUCUGCUAGCCAGGAUCCACAAGUCCUUGUUCCACUGUGCCUUGGUUUCUCCUUUAUUUCUAAGUGGAAAAAGUAUUAGCCACCAUCUUACCUCACAGUGAUGUUGUGAGGACAUGUGGAAGCACUUUAAGUUUUUUCAUCAUAACAUAAAUUAUUUUCAAGUGUAACUUAUUAACCUAUUUAUUAUUUAUGUAUUUAUUUAAGCAUCAAAUAUUUGUGCAAGAAUUUGGAAAAAUAGAAGAUGAAUCAUUGAUUGAAUAGUUAUAAAGAUGUUAUAGUAAAUUUAUUUUAUUUUAGAUAUUAAAUGAUGUUUUAUUAGAUAAAUUUCAAUCAGGGUUUUUAGAUUAAACAAACAAACAAUUGGGUACCCAGUUAAAUUUUCAUUUCAGAUAAACAACAAAUAAUUUUUUAGUAUAAGUACAUUAUUGUUUAUCUGAAAUUUUAAUUGAACUAACAAUCCUAGUUUGAUACUCCCAGUCUUGUCAUUGCCAGCUGUGUUGGUAGUGCUGUGUUGAAUUACGGAAUAAUGAGUUAGAACUAUUAAAACAGCCAAAACUCCACAGUCAAUAUUAGUAAUUUCUUGCUGGUUGAAACUUGUUUAUUAUGUACAAAUAGAUUCUUAUAAUAUUAUUUAAAUGACUGCAUUUUUAAAUACAAGGCUUUAUAUUUUUAACUUUAAGAUGUUUUUAUGUGCUCUCCAAAUUUUUUUUACUGUUUCUGAUUGUAUGGAAAUAUAAAAGUAAAUAUGAAACAUUUAAAAUAUAAUUUGUUGUCAAAGUAA